GCCGGGGAGUUUUGUUCCAUUUCCCGGAUCCUGGGGUCUGGAGGCGAAAUAUGCUCUGGGCGAGGACCACCGGGUGUGGGAAGAGGGUUCUGAGCGUCUCCUGACGUUGACGGUUUAUUUCCUAGAGUGUGUUGGGUCUUUCUGUGAGGGUUUCGAGAAGGAAACAGGCAUGCGACUGGUUCAUGCAGCGGACACCCGGUGGGAGGCCUGGGCCUCUGCGGUUUAAUCCAGCAGGGGGAUGGGGCUCAUUCCGCAAUUUAAAGAGAGAAAUAAGUUGGCUCCAGAGGGUUGGUUAUUUUAAGAUUAAUGACCUUCGGAUUCUUCUUUCUGCUCUAUUGUUUACUUUCUGUGCAGCGUACGCGUCCUUUUUCCUAAGAGCGCCCUAAACAAGAAUUGAAAAUGAAGCAAUUCCUGGCUAAAAUAUUCCUUAACAUGAAGAUCGCUGAGGCCCCAAAGACUCAUUAGUUUCCCGAGGUCACAGACUAAUUUUACUAACCACACAACCUUUAGAAUUUCAGUCUCCUCCCACAUGAAGAAACGCCGGCACCUUACACCGACAGGAAAACUACAAUUAAGUGAGGCUGUUCUCCUCAAGCCCGACUGAGUUCUCUGUAAUUGUAGGGCAUACCUACACCCUGUUUUAGCAUUAUGAGACCUGAAAUACUUUUAAAUUACUGGCACCAUUUCUCAUCUCUGAAUUAUAAGUUUAUAAUGCUCUAUCCCUUCCAGUGUUAUUGACUACAUGCAUUAUUCAUAGAUAAGUAGUAGGACUAAGCUAGUCUUUGUGGGUUAAAGUGUUAUUAUCCCUAUUGUAACCUGUAACUAUUAUAGGUUGUGUAAUAGUUAUUAGCAUUUUACAUCCAUAUCCUGGUAGCAAGAUAAAAACAUUUUAAUAGCGACUUCGUACAGAGUUCUUACUCAGUUUACCAUAGCUGUUUGAUAUGAAAGUUAAGGCUUCCUUUUAAAUUAGUUUCAGUAAAACUAAUGUUUAAUGAUAAAACACCUCAGUCAACUCAAGUUAGGAUUCAUCGGGGUAAGGAGAUAGUUCAGUAAUCCCAAGUUACCUUAAAAUAGUGGGCUUUUAGAGGAAAGGCUUUACUGAAGCUCUCACUGUAUCUACCCCAUGGGGAACAAUGAUUAACAACUUUGGCCACCACAUAACCCCCAGUAAAAUGACAAUUUUCCAUUAGCCUGGAACUGGAACUGGUUAAGUCCUAACUCCUUAGCCUAGAAUGACAGGGGGAAAAAACUAUCAAUGGGGACUGCAACCGCUGUCUCAUCCAGCGCACACAUCCAAGUUUUCAGAAUAAUAGGGGGCUUCUCUUAGUCCUUAACUCUUGGCUCUUUACUUAAAACAGUAACCUCCAUGACUUCAUGCAGAGUUCAGGAGCAGCCUCAGGGCCCUGCUGAACUCAAAAUUGUUUAUUCACUACAUUGUGAACCCAAGGAGACCUAUUUCUCUUAGUGGCUAAAGUAAACCUAAAUGCUUCAAGGUCAACUGCAUAAAGAUAAACUGCAUUGCCUGGUGUGGUGGCUCACGCCUGUAAUCCCAGCAUUUUGAGAGGCCAAAGUGGGUGGAUCACGAGGUCUGGAGAUGGAGACCAUCCUGGAUAACACAGUGAAACCCCGUCUCUACUAAAAUAAUACAAAAAAUUAGCCGGGCGUGGUGAUCAGCACCUGUAAUCCCAGCUGCUCUGGAGGCUGAGACGGGAAUCGCUUGAACCCGGGAGAGGGAGGUUGCAGUGAGCCAAGAUCGCACCACUACACUCCAGCCGGGUCAACAGAGCAAGACUCCGUCUCAAAAAAAAAAAAAGAUAAACUGCAUUAAUUCAUAUAAGUUAACAUAUCAAAGAAGAACAAAUUUGCCAUAGCCACACUAGUUACAUUUUUGCUGGGCAAGUGUUUUAUGAUACAUAAUUUGUAAAAAGACCAACAACUAAAAAGGACAACUUAAGCCAGGUCCCUGAAAGCUUUCACAAGUUACAAAUUGUGAAUUAAAUGAAGCUGUGCUGUUAGGCAUUAAACAGGUUAUAGUUUGCAAUUCGAAAUUACAUCUAUGUAUAUUUAAUUUUAAAUUAUGUGAAAAGAACAUGGUUCCGAAGAGGUGUUUUUUGUUUGUUUUGUUUUGAGACAGGGUCUCAAAAUGAAUUUUGCCCAGGUUGGAGUGGUGGAACAAUCACGGCUCACUACAGCCUCAACCUCCUGGGCUCAAGCGAUCCUCCCACCUCAGCCUCUCAAAUAGCUGAGACUACAGGCACACGCCACCAUGCCUGGCUAAUAUUUUUUUACUUUUAGUAGAGACAAGGUCUCACUCACUAUGUUGCCCAGGCUGGUCUCAAACUCCUGAGCUCAAGCCAUCCUCCAGCCCUGGCCUCCCAAAGUGCUGAGAUUACAGGUACAAGCCACCAUGCCCAGCCUAAGAAUCAUUCUUAGUAAGAUUAUUUCACGCUGCUAAUGGCUCUCUGCCAAAAGAAAAAAAAGGAAGUUUAAAGAAUGAAGUAGUUAAUAUAGUGGGUUAAAUACCCUCAUCUAAUUUUACUCCCUUCCAAAACUACUAAAUCUACAGUAAAAUGAUAUAAAAAUAAAUUGGAAAAAUGGGGACAGGAGGUAACAGCAAUAAAACUCAGAAGCUGGAAAACAGGUGAAUGAAUGUGACUUAGCACACCAGAAAAACCCAAUUCACUCUGCAGAAUUCUCAAAAGGCACUGAAACACGCACCCUGAAAUUGGAAGUGGACUACAUGAAAGCUAUUUGAGAAACACCUCUAAGUAACUCUACCCCCUUACUCCCAUAGAAGACUAGAGGUUUAUUUCUGGACAAAGUAAUACUAGUCCCUGGACUGGGGCAUCCUCAGGCAUUCUAGAGAAGCACACUGGAAACAAAGUUAAGUGAAUUUAGGAAUACAUAAUGCUGGAUGCAGGGCCCGCAUUCCUCUUAUCCUUAGAAGACUGGAAGACUCAACUCUGAGGAACUGACCAGCCCAGGAGGAGCAAUCCAAGAUAGUGACAUCAGAGGUUCCCCAGUAAAGGCCCACCCAGAGCACCCUAAGUGAAGCCCAGAGUCUAUAUGCUUCACCCACGUAUACAGAUCUAAAAAGCUUUUUUGUCUUUUCAUUCAUAAGAGUAGACAGAAAAGAAUGACCAGACUUUGGAAGAAAGCUCAGAAGUGAUAGAGACAGAAGCAAGCAGAAAAGCAAUUUGAAGUAAAACAGCUCAGAAGUGAUAAGAGACAAAAGCAAGCAGAAAAGCAAUUUGAAGUAAAACAACAGAAAAUUUCAAGAAAGCAAGAAUCAGUGAACUUGGAAAGAAAAAAUGCCUACAUAAUAUGCUUGUUAUGUGAAUUAGCUCAUUAACUAGUAGUAAGUACAAUUUAACAAGUAUUAAUGUAGAAGUAUUUUUUUCCCUAGGAAAGAGGAGCCAGAAAAGCAGUAAAUGUAUGACCUUCAGUUAAGAAAAGGUCAUGGCUUCACUGCUAUGCUGGCGGCAAGUGUCUUUCAGAUUUUUUCAUUGAUUCAAGUGUAUAUUCCAGGGUUCCUUCCCCAGAGAGGCAUACCCCAAGUUCUGUGUAGCCAUCGACUGAGGACAGGUAGAGUCACCUAUCCUACCCACGAAUUGGCAGCCUUGUGGUUUAGAUGGAUUUCUACUUCCAUGUGUUAUUUCAGCAUCUCUUAGCUCUGUUCUUAGACUUUGGCUGGCAUUUCUAUUAUUUUUUUAAGUUUUGCUGAAGUAGAAUUGACACUGAAUUACACUUACAAAGUAUAAUUCGAUAAAUUUGGUUCAUAUAUAUACACAUCUAUAUAUGCAUAUUUAUAGAUAUAUAUGUGCUAUAAUAUAUACUACAUAUAGUAUAAUAUAUAGUAUACAUAUUUUUGUUUCCAUAGAAACAAAAAUAAAAGGAAUUACUAUGUACUAUAUACUAUAUAUAUCUACUAUAUACUACGUAGUAUGUACUACAUAGUACAUAUAGUACAUAUAGUACAUACUGUACUAUGUAGUAUAUAGUAAUAUAUAUAGUACAUAACUAUAUAUGUACUACAUAGUACAUACUAUGUAGUAUAUGGUAGAUAUAUAUACCAUAGUAUACUAUAUACUAAAAAUGGCUGGCUACCUCUGUUUGUCAAUAUAUAUUUUAAUAUAUUUUUGCAAGUAAUAGAAAUGCCAGCAAAAGUCUAAGAACAGGGCUAAGUGGUGGGAAAACUACAUACUAUAUACUAUAUAGUAUCUAUACUAAUUAUAUAGAUUUGUAUAUAUACAUAUAUGUAUACAUACACACACACACACACACACACACACACAAUGAAGCCAUCACCACAAUCAAGACAAUAAAUAUAUCCACUAUCCACAAAGGUUGCCUUGUGCAUCUUUGAUUCCUUCCUGGUCUCCAGCCCCUACUCCCAUUCCCAGGCUACUCUAUUAUAAUUUUUGAGUAUUUUUAACAUCUCUAUAGUAGUCUCCAGCUAUGCUGAGAGCAAUCUGAGUGGUCAAAAUUAACUGUCCAGGAAGAGCAGAAAUGAACAACUCAGUAGAACACUUGGAAGAAGAAAAUGAGAAAAUCCCCCAUACAACUAAAUAAAAGGCUGGGCGCAGAGGCACACACCUGUUAUCCCAGCACUUUGGGAAACCAAGGAGAGUGGAUCACCUCAGGUCAGGAGUUCGAGACCAGCCUGGCCAACAUGGUGAAAAGCCAUCUCUACUAAAAAUACAUAAAUUAGCCAUGCUUAGUGGCAGGCACCUGUAAUUCCAGCUACUUGGGAGGCUGAGGCAGGAGAAUCACUUGAACCCAGGAGGCGGAGGUUGCAAUGAGUUGAGAUCAGGCCAUUGCUCUCCAGCGUGGGUGAUAAGAGCGAAACUCCAUGCUUAAAAAAAAAAGACAAAUGGAAAAUAGUACAGAAAAAAGGAAGAGAACAUGUUUAGAAGUUCAAACAUCCAAAUAAUAAAAGUUCCAGGAAGGGAGAAAAAAGAAAAUGGAGGAGGGAGGAAAUCAUGAAUGAAAUCAUUUAAAAUUUUUUCCCAAAUUGAAGGAAACAAGUGUCCAGAUUGCAAGGGCCAACUGAGUGUCCAGUACAAUGGAUAAAAAUAAAUCCAUUAUCAACACAUCACUAACAUUUCAAAAUCUUCAUGGAGAAGAUUCUGUAAGUUUCUGGGGAGAGAGAGAAAAAAUACAUCACAUACAGAGGAUCACUUACCAGGACUGCUUUGAACUUAAUAGCAAUGGUAAAAGCAAACAGACGAGCAACUACUUCAAAAUGUUGAAAAGAAAAUUAUUUCCAGCUUUCAAUUCUAUACUCAGACAAGCUAUCAAACAGAUAGAGGGAGCCAGCCAUUUUUAGACAUCCAGGGUCUCAUUUACCUUCCAUGUACCCUUUUCAAGAAGUUAGGAUGUGCUCCACAGAAACAAAAAUAAAACCAGGAAAUGGAACACUUUGGAAUGUAGAAAAUGGGAUAAUCAACAUAGAGGAUAGGCAAGAGGAAUUUCUGGGAGCAUGGUCAAGUAGGAUUCCAGCACCACAGUUGUGCUUCUUGAUGUAGAGAGCAGUCAGUCCAGAAUCAAGCAGCAUGACUCACAUUGAUGGCUAUUAUCACUAAGAUCCCUGCUGCCAUUGUAUCAUCUUUUUAAUCUGAGGACAUUAUGCCCAGGCAAGCCUGGCUCAGAUUCUUACCGGUAUUUGCCUUGUCUUGACCAUGUGGUGAUGAAAUUCCUGCUCUCUUCUGUGCUGUGCUGACUGGACCAACUGAGGACACUCAUUUUUACCCUUCUUUUUCAACCUAUUCCUGAAAGCUGAUGUUGGGCGUUGGUGAGCUUAAAGCAGAAAAUAGCCUUCCUCCUUCCCAUUUUUGCUAUGUAUUGGCCAGAAAUCAGGUAUCAAUUCUACACUUUGAUCUUUCCACAUGCUUCAGUUGUGAGGAGCCCAGUAUUCACUCAUGACAUUGCAAAUUAACUUCUCUAGAAGGGAUCCAGAAAGCCUGGAGAAGGUAAAGCCAGACUAGGGCUGUUUGGCUUUAAUUAACAGCAGCAUUGUUGCCCUUUUCCUUGCUAGAUUCGUGCUUGCUGCUCAAAUUGCCAAAAUUAAAUAUUUAGGGCAAUGUUCAUGAGUGCUGGGAAAACUAAAGAGAAUAAGCAGGAAGUCAUUAGAGGCUAUCUUGGUAGAGAUGGGGAAGGAGAAGCAAUUGGAGAGGGGCACAUGGGGGCUUCUAAGACUUUUGUUUCAUAACUUGAAUGAUGGGUACCCAGAUGUAUAUUUUACUUUAAUUUGUACAUUCAUAUUUUAUGCAGUUUCUAUGUCUAAUACGUAUAAAAAUUUCAGAUUAAAUGAAAUACAUGAAGGCACUGGCACCCUGCCUUUCAAAUUGUAAAAGGUGUAAAUUUUGCAAAAUGCCUAAAGGGGCAGGUGAGGUCACAAUGAGAAUCUACACUAUUGUACUUCGGGGUUCAACCCAAACAGAAGUUAACAGGAGAACUUAAAUUAUGUAGCGCAUGAUUUUUAAUUGAGUAUGGUACUGUAAUUUUAAUCCACAUUUUCUGCUAGUUAACUAUAAAAUAACCCUUAAAACUGAUCUAAAAGCCUAUUUUAAAAAUAUAAGUUGCGGCCGGGCACGGUGGCUCACGCCUGUAAUCCCAGCACUUUGGGAGGCCAAGGUGGGUGGAUCACAAGGUGAGGAGAUCAAGACCAUCCCGGCCAACAUGGUGAAACCCCGUCUCUACUGAAAUACAAAAAAAAAAAAAAAAAAAAUUAGCCAGGCGUGGUGGCGCGCACACGUAGUCCCAGCUUACUGGGGAGACUGAGGCAGGGGAAUUGCUUGAACCAGGGAGGUGGAGGUUGCAGUGAGCUGAGAUGGCACCACUGCACUCCAGCUUGGGGACAGAGCAAGAAUCCAUCUCAAAAAAAAAAAAGUUGCUUCCUGCUUGCCUAUCAGAGUAAUUCAGUCCAAAAGUCAUUACGUGGGGCUGAGCAAGGCAGGCAUCUGGGGAAGGUGGGGGCGAGAGAAAGGCUGGCAAGGUAGUAGCCCAGCAGGGGAUACUGGAGCCCAAAUGCAGUGAGGAGGGCCUCUGGGGGUAGGGACUUGUGCACAGCAGCAGCCUAGCAGGGGAUGAGGAGGGCAUCCUAUUAGGGUGAAGGAAAUGGUGGCACAGGUUUUUGGAAUGGGAACAAAAGGUGAGCCUUACCCAGGAGGGAGGAAAUGGUGCAGUGUAAGUUGCUUGAGCCCAAGAAGGGUAGGUUGGGGGAAAGGGGGAAGAGAAGACCAUGCAUGUGGGAUGGUGGCAGUGGCACUCUGGCAUUAGGUGGCAGAGCUCAGAGAGUAGAGUGUGUGCGCCGAAUGGUGACAGCAAGAGGAUUUUGAUUACAUAGUGAGAGAAGGGGUGAUGAUUAUAAAAAGUAAAUUUAUUAAGGACAAGUGGGAACCAGACUUCUCACUGUUCAGCAAGAGUAUUAAACCCAUGUAAAGAGGGGAAAUGAAAAUAAACCCUGUAGUAUUGGAAUUGAAUGUUAGGUAGCAGAUUAUAUGGAGAUUAAUAUAAAAGUCAUACACACAUACAACACCUAAAUCCGUAUGUAUAUACACUUGCAGCUUUGUCACUUAGAGGACCUGGGAACAGUGACAGUCCCAUGGUGAUUAGCAUUUUUAGCACCCAGACCUUGGUUUCUAAAGCAUUCCAUCCAGAUUAUAGUUUCUAAAUGCUAUUCUCCAUUAAAAGGACUAGGUUCCUUGGAGAAAUAAUUUUACAAUGGACAAUCUUAGCAAAUACAUUAAUUGGGUAAUCAAAGUUAUCAAUCACAAUGGAACAAAUUGCAGUUGCAUCCACCUGAUAGGAUGCAAUGUUAAGAGCUUACUAUUCAACUCUAACAGGUAGUGGGAAUUAUUUUCUAGGUUUAGACUGUCAUGAUGCCUUUAAGUUUGGAGCCUCCUCUACAAAGUAGAGUUAACACAUUACACAUAAAGAAGCAUGAUUUUGCCUGUUCCUCAGGGACACCCUCUUACAGGUUGUUCAUUUGGCCUCUUCACCACCAAUCUUACUGCCCAUCUACUAUUCCAACCUGCUUAACUCACCCAGUUUCUGCUAGUUUUCAGCCUCCCUUUGGAUAAGCACCCAUCAGCAUUUGAUCAGGCUUCUGCUCAAUGUCCUUCAAGUGGCUCUGGCCUUGCCUUGAGAGCAGGGUAAAGAUAAUCUCUUGUUUGUUGAUAAGGAAAACUCAGGCUCAGCAAGGUUAAUUAAUCUGUACAUUAUGCAACUGGAAUUUAAAUCUAGUUUAACUCAUUCCACUGUGGCAUAAAAGGAGGUACACGUACCUAUCUGUGAUGACAAUCCACUUUCUCAUUUCCUUCAUGUGACUUCUCACAAUCACAAUUGUCUUUGCUUAUGUCUCCCAUAGGAAAACGUCAAUUAUGACAGCAGGUAAUUUUAUCGGAAGUGUUUAUAACUAUAUCCCAGUACGUGGAACGAAAAAGUUAUCAAGAAAUAUUUAUUGAAUGUAAAAAAGGUAUGUUAUGCAUAAAAGUGGAUAAUUUACAUGAUAAAUGAAAAUGGCCAAUUCUUUAAGAGGAGAAGUACUAAAACUUUAUAAAAAUCUGCUGUAUCUUGGACGAGACUAUCCAAAAGGAGCAGACUAUUUUAAAAAGCGUUUGAAGAACAUUUUCCUUAAAAACAAAGAUGUGAAGAAUCCAGAGAAGAUCAAAGAACUUAUUGCACAGGGCGAAUUUGUAAUGAAAGAGCUAGAAGCUUUGUACUUCCUUAGGAAAUACAGAGCUAUGAAACAACGCUAUUAUUCAGAUACCAACAAAACUAAUUGAUCAUUACUACUUUAAUUUAGCUAUCAGUGCCAGCUGUUUAUGUAUACCAGAUGUUGUAAAAUAAUUCUAACUUAAAAUGGGAAGAUAUACAUGUUGUGUAAAAAAUCCCUGAGCUGCCCUACUGAACUAAAUAGGUUUCAACUUCUGUUCAUACGGAGAAAGUAUCAGCAACUUUAUGCUCAAUUUUGAUACAAACAUAGCAAUUUAGCUAUACUACCGAUCAUAAAUUAAUGAGCACCCAAUUUUGAAUGAAAAUAUAAUACACUUAAUCCUCUAACUUAAUAGGACUUAGCCAAUUAUUUUUAGCUUAUUUCUCCAUUUUACUGACAAGAGAAUGCCAUUUACCGAACAUUUAAUAAGCAAAAUAAUUUCUUACACACUUACUUCUCUUAACUUUUGAAAGGAAUCCCUUAUUUUUUCACCCAAUUUGGUAUAUUAACAGCACAUACUCAAGGUUCACUACAAAACAAACAGUUCCUGGUAAUGAUUUAAAUGUAGUUAUAGAAAUAAAUAAUAUGUAUGGAGUCAUUACUUCUGACCUUGAAAUAGCCUGCUGGUGACUGGCAUUAACAUACAUAACUAACUAUUCAAUUAUUUCCAUUAUUAAUGUUGCUGCUGCUACCUUUGGGCCUAAAACCAAGUCACCUGUUGUGUAUCAAUUACCUUCUUUGAUAAAAGGAAAUAAAUAAAUAAUGUUAUCCUAUUUUUUUGUCAUAAAGGCAGAUUUGUUUUGCAUCUACUUCUAAAUAUGGUUUUAAGUUUAAGCAAACACGCCUUUACAUAAUAUCCACAGCACCUUUUAGAAAUAAAGGAUACUUCUAACAAGCUGCA